AUGGCAUCUUCUGCAGAGCUGGACUUCAACCUGCAGGCUCUUCUGGAGCAGCUCAGCCAGGAUGAGUUGAGCAAGUUCAAGUCUCUGAUCAGAACAAUCUCCCUGGGAAAGGAGCUACAGACCGUCCCCCAGACAGAGGUAGACAAGGCUAAUGGGAAGCAACUGGUAGAAAUCUUCACCAGCCACUCCUGCAGCUACUGGGCAGGGAUGGCAGCCAUCCAGGUCUUUGAAAAGAUGAAUCAAACGCAUCUGUCUGGGAGAGCUGAUGAACACUGUGUGAUGCCCCCACCUUAA